GUAGUCUUGACGUGAGCUAGCUGGCAUGGCGGCCUGCAUUGCAGCGGGGCACUGGGCUGCAAUGGGCCUAGGCCGGAGUUUCCAAGCCGCCAGGACUCUGCUCCCCCCGCCGGCCUCUAUCGCCUGCAGGGUCCACGCGGGGCCUGUCCGGCAGCAGAGCACUGGGCCUUCCGAGCCCGGUGCGUUCCAACCGCCGCCGAAACCGGUCAUCGUGGACAAGCACCGCCCCGUGGAACCGGAACGCAGGUUCUUGAGUCCUGAAUUCAUUCCUCGAAGGGGAAGAACAGAUCCUCUGAAAUUUCAAAUAGAAAGAAAAGAUAUGUUAGAAAGGAGAAAAGUACUCCACAUUCCAGAGUUCUAUGUUGGAAGUAUUCUUCGUGUUACUACAGCUGACCCAUAUGCCAGUGGAAAAAUCAGCCAGUUUCUGGGGAUUUGCAUUCAGAGAUCAGGAAGAGGACUUGGAGCUACUUUCAUCCUUAGGAAUGUUAUCGAAGGACAAGGUGUCGAGAUUUGCUUUGAACUUUAUAAUCCUCGGGUCCAGGAGAUUCAGGUGGUCAAAUUAGAGAAACGGCUGGAUGAUAGCUUGCUAUACUUACGAGAUGCCCUUCCUGAAUAUAGCACUUUUGAUGUGAAUAUGAAGCCAGUAGUACAAGAGCCUAACCAAAAAGUUCCUGUUAAUGAGCUGAAAGUAAAAAUGAAGCCUAAGCCCUGGUCUAAACGCUGGGAACGUCCAAAUUUUAAUAUUAAAGGAAUCAGAUUUGAUCUUUGUUUAACUGAACAGCAAAUGAAAGAAGCUCAGAAGUGGAAUCAGCCAUGGCUUGAAUUUGAUAUGAUGAGGGAAUAUGAUACUUCAAAAAUUGAAGCUGCAAUAUGGAAGGAAAUUGAAGCGUCGAAAAGGUCUUGAUUCUGAGAAUGAAUUUGGUUAGUUGCAGAAGAUACAUUGGCUCUAAGAGGAUAUAUUUUGAGACCAAUUUAAUUUCAUUUAUAAGAACAUAGUAAUUAAGUGAACUAAGCAUUCAUUGUUUUAUUAAUACUUUUUUUCUAAAAUAAAACUUGUACACCAGUUUAUUACUCUAAAAAGAGAAUUACACAUGCCAAAUGGACCAAUGUCCAUUUGCUUAUUGGAGGCAAAGCUACAAUAGAAGUCAGAGCAUCACCAGAAUGGUCUUUAAUGAGCAUGGAACCUGAGCAAAGGGAAUAGGUGGGAUGAAUUUUUUUUUUAAUUGUGAAACAAUUCAUAAGCACAAUAUGAUUUACAGAAUAAUAAACAUUCAUGUACCCACUAUCAGGUUAAGAAAUAGAACAUUUAUUAAUAUGUAGGAAUGUUAAGAAAUAAAACAUUUAAUAAGAUCUCAGAAGACUCCAGUAAAUCUGCAAUUGUAUCUCUCUCCUUUUUAAAUGUAAAUAUCAUCUUGACUUGUUAAUUAUUCCCUUGCAUUUCUUUUAGUUUACUGCCAACACAUAUAUUCUUCAACAAUAUAUUUAAUUUUGAAAAACCUGAAAAAAAAAACCUGUUAGCAAGUAUAAAGGGGCAGUAUUACUAUUAUUGCAUGAAGGCUUCAAGGGAAACGUUACAGUCUUUGGGUCAUAGUCUGGCUUCAGCUUCCUCUGAGAGUUUACAGAGGCCAAUUUUGAGCAAAUUCAUGGCUAAGGUUAUGAGUGAGUUCUGCUAAACAGAAGGCUCACCACAAGGUAUCUGGCAGGAUUAUACUGGGUAGCUGGAUGUUGCAGAAAUGUGGUUAGAGGAAGUAAACUGUUUUUUGAUGCUCACAGCAUGAUGAAUCAAACUCUGUAUCUUAGGAUUAGGUUAAAACAAUACCUUUGGUAUGAUAUGAGUGUUGUUGCUGAUCCAUGCAGCAUGGAUUGGAAAGCUGGGGUAUAAGCACACAUGCUAAAGAAAAACAUGUAAUUUGGUCCAUACUCACCUGGAUAUACUGUUCCUCAGGUUAAAAAAUACAGUACUAUCCUAAAUCUUGAAGGCAACUCUCAGCCUAUCCAUUGAGUUACCUUCAGAUCUGCCCUCUGGUUCCUAGCUGUCUUGGGACUAACUUCUUUCCUGCGCUCAGCUGUUUUCUGGAUUCCAUGUUUUCCAUUUUAUUGAGUACUAACUUGUUUUGCUGCAGCACAUCCUUUGGUAGCUUCUAGAGGAAGUUUGUGUGGAGGUAAAAUUUUUGAGACCUUGCAUGUCUCAUGUUUGAUUGAUACUUUAUACGUUUAGGUAGGAGGUAAUUUUCCUUCAGGACUUUAAAAAUAUUGUUGCUCCAUUUUCUUUGUUUCUAUUGUUGUAUUGAGAAAUCCAAUGCCAUUUUGAUUUCCCCAUCAUAAAUUUCAUGAUGAUGUGUCUUGGUGUGGGUCUAUAUUUAUCCAUUGUAUUGGGUUUUAGGUGAACCCUUCCAGAUAGUAACUCAUUUCUGUCAGUUCUGGGAAACACUUAGCAUUGGUUGAUGAUUUAUUCUCUGCUGCUUUGUUCUCCCAACUAUUAUUUGGAUGUUGGAUAUCCAGCACUGGGUAUCUAUUUUCUUACCUCCCUCCCUUGACCCCAGUCUCUGUUUUUUAGCUCUUUAGCUCAAUCUUCCAACUCUUUGCUAUUGUAUUUUAAAAUCUUAAGACCCCUUCUUGAUUUGUAGAAGUUCCUUUUCUUACAACCAAAAAGCCUUUAUCUAUGGAUUUGUUCACAGAUAAGGGGUAUUCAAUAUAGUGUAUUUUUUUUUCAUUUAAAAUUGUUUGCGCAUCUAUUUCCUCCAAAUUUCUUUCUGUAUUUAUUUUUUGUUGUCUAUAUUUCAGACUUUUCCAGGAUAUCUGAUAAUCUUUGGCUGUCUUCUUAUGGUUGAAAGAGGGACUAAAAAGCUUGGAAAGCCUUUGGGUUGUGGGAAGGGGCUGUCUUUAGGAUUAUCUGAAUGGGCUUUUUUGGGAGUCCCCUCCUCCACAUGAAUAUUUUGGUUUUGUCAGAUUCCCUAGAAUAGAGGCUUCCAAUCUCCUUCCUGGAGGGGUCUGUCCAGGAAGGAGAUUGUCUAGGGGUCUGUCAGACAGCAGCUUUCAGCUACUUCCUUGAUCUUUUUCACUAAUGAUUAUAUAGUCAUCUAACUACUGUCAACAAGUAAUAGAUAUCCUAUCCUUCACUUGUUUAGAUUAUUUGCUGAGAUAACCUCUCAAAAGAACCUCUCAAAAUAAAAGGUUAACAAGAGCCUAUAUCUUAUAUUUUUCUUCUCUUUAUCUUGUUAGAAGAUAGCUAUUAAAACCUGUUCUUUUUCUGUCUUGAUAAACACACUUCAAUCUUGGUAGAAUGGUAGAUGGGACAGUAUAUUUUAGGACCUAAAGCUCUGCAAAUGUAUGAUCAGCUUGUAAGUACAGGUGCUCAAAAACAUGUAAACAAUCAUGCUUUUUACUCUGUAGGAAUAUCUUUAAAAUUCUUGUGAAUUUUUCCCCAGAAGUAAAGCAAAUCUUCCCCCAGAAAUAAAAUUAAAUGUGCAUAAUCUAAAGCUUUUUUUUUUUAUUGUGGUAGGAUAUAUAUAUAAAACAUAAUUUGCCAUUGUAAACAUUUUAAAUUUACAAGUCAGAGGCAUUAAUUACAUCACAAUGUUGUGAAAUUAUUACUACUAUUUCCAAAAUUUUCUCAUCACCCCAAACUGAAACUCUGUAACUGUUGAGCAAUAACCUCAUUCCUGUAUCUCUCCCAACCCCAGGUAACCUCAAAUCUUUCUUUUUAUCUUUGAGACAAGGUCUCAUUCUAUCACUCAGGUAGGAGUGCAGUGGUGUGAUCAUAGCUCAUUGCAGCCUCAAAAUCCUGGGCUCAAGCAAUCCUCCUUGAGUAGCUAAGACUAUAGGCACACAUUAACUGCGCCUGGCUGAUUUUGUUUUUUGUAGAGAUGUGGUCUUGCUAUGUUUCCCAUGCUGGUCUUGAGUUCCUGGCCUCAAGCAGUCCUUAAGAUUCAUCCAUGUUGUGGCAUGUGUCAGAAUUUCAUUUGUUUUUAUGACUAAAUAAUAUUCCAUUGUAUGUAUAUACAUUUUGUUCAUCCAUCUUCUGAUGAACACUGGGAUAUGUCUACCUUUUGGCUAUUGUGAAUAAUGCUGCAGUAAACAUUGACAUAACAAGUAUGUAUUUGAUUGCCUGUUUCUAAGUUCUUUUGGGUAUACAUCUUGAGUAGAAUUGCUAGAUAAUGUCAUGUUUUAUUUCUCUUGUGAUUUCUUCUUCGAUCCCCUGGUUGAGUGUGUUAAUUUCUACAUGUUUAUGAAUUUCCCACUGUUUUUUUGUUAUUGAUUUCCAAGUUCAUUCCAUUGUGAUUAGAGAAGAUACUUAGUAUGAUUUUAAUGUUUUUGAGAAUUGGUGUGUGGCCUGAUAGAUGGUCUGUCCUGGAGAAUGUUCCUCAUACACUUGAGCAAAAUAUUUAUCAUGCUAUUGUUGACUGUAGUUUUCUAUAUGUCUCUUAGGUCAAGGUGGUUUACAAUGUGUUAAGGUUCUCUUUUUUUAAAAAAAUUUUUGCACAGAGUAUCUUUUUCUAUGUGUUCCAUGUAUUUGUGUCUUUGGAGCUAUAGUCUCUUGUAGACAGCAUAUCACUAUCUUGUUUUGUUUUGUUUUUUCUGUCCAUUCUGCCAAUUUCUGCCUUUUGAUUGGAAAAUUUAAUCCAUUUGCAUUUAAAGUAAUUAAGGAAGGACUUUCUUCUACCAUUUAACACUUCUUCUAUAUGUCAUAUACUUUUUUGGCCCCUCAUUUCCUCUUUAUGGCCUUCUUUUCUGUUUUUUUGUAGUGAACUAGUCUGAUUCUCUUUCCACUCCCCUUUGUGUAUAUUUGUUAGAUGUUUUAUUUGUGGUUGCUAUGGGGAUUAUAGUUAACAUCCUACACUUAAAACAAUCUAAUUUAAACUGAUACCAAUUUACCUUCAAUAGCAUACAAAAUCUCUACUCCUGUAAAGCUCUGCCCCUGCCCCCCUUAUGUUAUUGAUGGCACAAAUUGCCUAAUAAAUAAUUUAUAGUUAUUUGUAUGAGUUUGUCUUUUAAAUCAUUUAGGAAAUAAAAAGUGGAGUUAGAAAACAGUAUGAUAGUAAUACUGACUUUUAUAUUUGUCAAUAUAUUUAUCUUAUUUUGGAUCCUUAUUUCAUUAUAUAGAUUUGAGUUACUGUCUAGUGCCCUUCCAUUUCGGCCCAAAGGAUUCCCUUAUGCAUUUCUUGCAGGGCAAGUCUAAUUGUAAUAAACUCCCUCAGCUUUUGUUUUAUCUGAGAAUGUCUUGAUUUCUCCCUUAUUUUUGAUGGAUAAUUUUGCCAGAUACAUGAAUUUUUGGUAACAGUAUUUUUCUUUCAGCACUUUAAAUAUGUCAUCCCACUACCUUCUGACUUCAUGGUUUCUCAUGAGAUAUUAGAUGUUAUAAAAUUUGAGGAUUCCUCAUUCUUGAUGAGUCAGUUCUGUCUUAUUGCUUUUCGGAUUUGCUCAGCUUUUGUCUUUUGACAGUUUGAUUAUAACGCGGCUCAGUGUGGGUCUCUGAGUUUAUCCCACUUAGAGUUUGUUGAGUUUCUUGGAGUCAUAGAUUUAUGUCUUUUAUCAAAUUUUGGACAUAUUUGGCUAUUAUUUCUUCAAUUUUUUUCACUGCUUCUUUCUUUUCCUUCUGAAAUAUUCUUAAUGUAUAUGUUGGUCUGUUUGAUGCUGUCUCACCAGUUUCUUAGGCUGUGUUCUCUUUUGUUCCUCAGACUUGAUUAUUGCAGUUGCCCUUCUUUUUAUUUUUUUCAAGUUUGUUGAUUCUUCUCCCUGUUCAGAUCAACUGUUGAACUCCUCUAGUGAAUUUAUUUCAGUUACUGUACUUUUCAGCUCCAAGAUUUAUCUUUGGUUCCUUUUUAUAACGUCUGUGUCUUUAUUGAUAUUCUCAUUUUGUUCAUAUGUCUCUUUCUUCCUUUAGUUCUUUGUCCAUGUUUUCCUUUAGCUCUUUGGGCUUAUUUAAGACAAUUGUUUAAAGUCUUUGCAUAGUAAGUCCAAUGUCUGUGUUUCUUCAGGGAUGGUUUUCAUUAUUUUGUUUUCAAUGAGCCAUACUUUCCUGUGUCUUUGUAUGCUGUCUUUUUGUUGUUGAAAACUGUAUGUUUGAACAUCAUAACGUGGUGGCCCUGAAAAUCAGAUAUUCCCCCCUUCCUGAGAGUUAGUUUUAUUUUUAUUAUUGAAGAUUGUAGCAGUCUAUUGCUACAUGUGCAGUCAUUUCCAAACUAUUUUUGCAAAGACUGUAUUCCUUCUGUGUGUCAUCACUGAAGUCUCUGUUCCUUAGUUUGUGUUUAAUAGUUUGACAUAGAUUUCCUUGAAAGGAGUUAAAACUAGCAGAAAAAUCUCUCUCCCAGUCUUUCCAGUCUUUGUAGAUUGGUUCUGUGCUGGGCUUUUCCAUUAAUACUUAGCCAGGCUUGUACUGAGCCUAACAAUCAGGCCCAAAAGCGUAGGGUCUUUGCAGAUCUUGUCUGAGCAUGCUUCUUGCUGUGUAUGCACGUAGUUUUCUAAAUCUCCCUGUAUGUGCUGUUGAAUAUUCUAAUUUCCCAAAGAAACUCCUUUGCAGCUUUUUCUCACAGAACAUAGAUGGUUUUUUGGAUAUCUUGACCAUAGUCUUUCGACCCAGGUGUUUGCGGUUGUUAGUUCACCUUACACUUUUUUCAAGCAUUGCCUACUGCUUACGAUGAGUGCUCUGUCAAUCCUUUAAGUAGCCCCAGACAGGCUACCAGAGACUUAAACAAGAAUUUGUAAGUUCUGCUCAGCUUCCUCUAGAAAUGGGGAUCAGGGUCCAAGACAGAAUGCAGUUGCUGAUUUCAAGACUGCUGCAACACCAGGGAGCUUGUGGGGGAAGGGCAAGCAGAAAUGUCACAAAGCUUUCUUGCCAUUUUAAAGUUGCCUGUUCUUGACUCAGCAUUUGCUUCAUUGCUAUAAACUUUUUACUGUUUUUCAGAGUUCUGAUAAAAUUGGCUAUGCCUGUUCCUGCUUUAAAAAAUAUAUAUAUAUUUUUUAGGGAUUGGGGUCUCACUAUACUGACCAGGCUGGUCUUGAACUUCUGGCCUCAAGCCAUCCUCUCAUUUCAGCUUCCCAAAGUGCUGCAAUUACACGCGUGAACCACCACACCCAGCCCCUGCUUGUUUUUCAAUGUGCCUACUCCACCAUGUUGCUCAAGUAUGUAUAUUUUCUAAACUACCUUGUAGUGUUGUGAUGGGAAAUAAAUCCCUGAGCCUUUUGAAUAACUCAGAGAGAUCAAAAACUUAGUUUAUCCUAUUCGAAGGAUUAGAAAAAUGAUAUAUCUUUCACUUUUUCAGGGAUAGGCUCCUCAUUAGAAGGCUCCUAUGUGCCGAUGCUGUACAAGACAUUUCAUUUCUCUUAAUGUUUACAACAAGCUUGUUGCCAAGGCUGAUCUUGAACUCCUGGCCUCAAACGAUCCUCCCAGCUCAGUCUCACAAAGUGUUGGGAUGUCUGGCCAACUAAUGACUAUCUUAACUCUUGUGUUUCAAUGUUUAUGCCUUCUUUUAUCUUGACUGAUUGUAUGACUAUGUCUUCUAGAACAAUGUUGAACAGAAAUGGUGAGAGCAGACAUCCUUGCUUUAAUAUUUCACCAUUAUAUAUGAUGUUAGGUAUAGAUUUUUCUCACAGAUGCCUUUUAUCAGAUUGAGGAAUUUAUAUUCCUACUUUGCCGAAAGGUUUUUGUAGUAUGAGGGGGUGCUGAAUUUUGUCAAACACUUUUUCGGUAAUAAUUGAGAUGAUUGGUUCUGCAGUCAUCGAGAUGUGGAUUUUCUCCUUUAUUCUGUUCGUGAGUGAUUACACUGGUUGACUAAUGUUAAAACAACCUUACUUUCCAGGAAUAAACCCUAUUAUCUUUUUUAUA